ACUAGGCUCUCAGCCAGGGAUGAUGCGCUGCUGCCGCCGCCGCUGCUGCUGCCGGCAACCACCCCAUGCCCUGAGGCCGUUGCUGUUGCUGCCCCUCGUCCUUUUACCUCCCCUGGCAGCAGCUGCAGCGGGCCCAAACCGAUGUGACACCAUAUACCAGGGCUUCGCCGAGUGUCUCAUCCGCUUGGGGGACAGCAUGGGCCGCGGAGGCGAGCUGGAGACCAUCUGCAGGUCUUGGAAUGACUUCCAUGCCUGUGCCUCUCAGGUCCUGUCAGGCUGUCCGGAGGAGGCAGCUGCAGUGUGGGAAUCACUACAGCAAGAAGCUCGCCAGGCCCCCCGUCCGAAUAACUUGCACACUCUGUGCGGUGCCCCGGUGCAUGUUCGGGAGCGCGGCACAGGCUCCGAAACCAACCAGGAGACGCUGCGGGCUACAGCGCCUGCACUCCCCAUGGCCCCUGCGCCCCCACUGCUGGCGGCUGCUCUGGCUCUGGCCUACCUCCUGAGGCCUCUGGCCUAGCUUGUUGGGUUGGGUAGCAGCGCCCGUACCUCCAGCCCUGCUCUGGCGGUGGUUGUCCAGGCUCUGCAGAGCGCAGCAGGGCUUUUCAUUAAAGGUAUUUAUAUUUGUA